ACACACACUCUUGUGUGUGCAGGAAGUCUAGGUCAACAGAGGGGUAGUGCAACCUAGGAUACAGUGUAGACUAGACAGCCAGGGACUGGACAAAAAUCCACUUCUCAGAGAAUGCCAGUCUAGAACAUAGCAAUGACCAAGAAUUAGAUGAUUGAUGUGUUUUCACCAAUGUCUGGCUGUCUCAUCAUAUCCUCAUGGGAAAAAAGAACUCUCUCUGGGAAGGCAGGUAUGUCUGAAAAAAUUCUUAUGUGACUAAAUCUACCUGGAAUUGGCAAGACAAAAUUUUCUCCUACUGAGUAGAAGAGAGAUCUGAAAUAGAACUCAAAUUCUGUUACAGGAAAAUAAAGGAGGUUCCAUUUCUUAUACCUGAGUUUGUGGCCUGUGAAAAUGCAUGACCAUUGUACAAAUAUAAAAUUUUCCAUCUGAGCUGCUACCAAUUGCAAUACAUAAUAGUUUUGCAUGAUGGUUAAGUAAUCCUUUAAGUAAAUUUGAAGAACAUGCUUUGCCCGCAAAAAUGGAAAAAAAAAAUCUAGAAAUCUUCUUGCCAAAGUCCAAAGACUUCUAAUGAAUAUUUCAAUUCAAUGUUGUGAGGCCCUAUAUUUUUGUUGAAUGGUGAAGUACGUGUGAUUCAUUAAGCUCUCAUUCAUUAUGAAAAUAGACUAGCAAAUUAUAUCCUUUGUAAGUAAAAUCAUUAUGAACAUAAUUUACAAAAUAGUUUAAGUUCUUUCAUGAUCUUUCUAAAGGAAAAGCCAAAUAGUUUUAAACACUUUGCAAGGGCAUUAUCAUUUAAAAAUCUUAGAUCUUACUUCUCGUUAGUUAUUUUUUGAAAUAUUUCUUGGGCAAAUAUCUAAAUUUGGUUGUAAUUUGCACAGUCUAAAGUAUUUUUUAUGUGUGCCCCAGAGAAUCAUGAUCACUAUGUUUUCGAGUGUAAAAGUAAAAAUGAAAUUCUGGUUUCUUACUGUAUUCAAAUGUUCUUUUCUUUUCCUCUCAAAUUUGUGUAAGCCUAUCUUGCCCCUUAGAGACUGUAACAUGAUCCUUCAUCUCUUCAAUUUUUGUAUUAAAUCAUUAUUUUUGAACUUGCAAAAGCAACAUAUAAGUCAGGCAGCAAGUUACAAGUUUAAAAUAAGCUGGCUUAACCCUCCAUGGGGUUUGAAAAUCAGUUAUCUACUUAAAUUAAGGUAGAAGUCAGAGCUGAUUUAGUGUCCUUCUAUGCUAUGCACACUCACAAUACUGUUCAUUACCACGAACAUGCCGGUACAUGUUUGUUUCCCAGGAAAAAUAGAGCCCUAUUCAUUAUUCAUAGAGGUCCUCCUGUACAGUAAAGACAUUCAUUCUCUAAUGGCUCUAUGACUAGGGUGUUGUGAAGCCCAAAGAUGUUUUUUUUGGAAGACAGUUUACCAAUUAAAAGCAAACAGCAUUGGAUUGCUUAGUAAUGUCCUCAACAUUGAUUGGCUGUGAUUGCAAAUGAACAUCAGGAGAAAUCCAAAGGCACAUCGCCGCCUGUUUCUAUGCUUGCUUGCUUGCUUCAGACACCUCCCUGGAAACAGAUCAUUAGUACAUGGAACUUCCAACCGGCUAGCUCAGACUUUUUUUUUUUUUUGCUUCAAGUAACUUAAAAAAUAUGCACCAGAUUUGCUUUCUCACAAACAUUUAAUUAUUUCCCCCUGAAAUGUAAUAAAAUGUGCGAAGUUAAUAUAGAAGCAAGUUUUAAAAAUGAUUGCCUGGAAGUGAGUUCAGAUUGUGAAGGCAAAUAGACCAUAUUCUUCAAGUAAAAAACAAUGAUGUGUUAUAUGAAGCUAAAUACAAUAGAAUUCUCUGUGGCUGAUAAAGAACAUAGGAUGUCAGCCUUACAUGUUUGAUGUAAAUUCAGCAAAAUUAAGCUUAGAUUUUGACUUACCAGUAAACAAUAGAGAUCAAGAUCAGUGCUAUUUUCCUAUCCAUAGGUCUAAAAAUUAUUAAUAGUUGAUAUUUAUUAUGCAGGCUGUAAACCCAGAAUGUGACACAGUUGGGCUUAAUGUAGUCACACAAUGGUUAGGAAACUUUCCUCAAUGUGGAAGAUGGAAGUAUGUUUGUGAUCAUUUUAAGGAAUCUAAACUAAAACAAAAUCACUUAUGCAUAAAAAUCUUAAUUGAAAAUGUUGGCAUUGACAAAGAAUAUGCCACAGGUUUGUCUGGCCAUAUGGCAGAGUUGUUUUCCUGACUUAGUAGAAAGCAGAUUUUAUUGCUUAGUUCUUGUACUUAUUCAUACUGAUGACUAAGUUGAAGAAACAAAUUUUCUUUGUCUUUCUGAUGUCCACGUAUAUUCACUCCAAUCAUGAAGGGGAAUGGUUGGAGUUUGAGAACCUACGUAAAUAAGAAUGGAAUAUUUUCUUUUAAAUGGCCUAAUAGAUGACAUUCAUUAUAAAAGAAUCAGACAUUAUAAAAGAAUCAGCCUGGUUGUUGGUAUGUUACCGGACUGAUGUUGUUGACUUGGUUCCAUUAAGAUUUUUGAGUUUUUCUUUGUAGAAUGGUAUAUUAAUAUCAUCAACCUGGCUGUUUUCUCCUACCCUGUCUUUCUUUCCUAUUUUUUUUUUUUUUUCUUUUUUAGACAGAGUCUCACUCUGUCACCCAGGCUGGAGUGCAGUGGUAUGAUCUCAGCUCACUGCAACCUCUGCCUACAGAGUUCAAGCAAUUCUCCUGCCUUAGCCUCCCGAGUAGCUGGGACUACAAACUCAUACCACCACGCCCAGCUAAUUUUUGUAUUUUUAGUAGAGAUGGGGUUUCACCAUGUUGGCCAGGCUGGUCUUGAACUCCUGAUCUCAUGAUCCACCCGCCUUGGCCUCCCAAAGUGUUGGGAUUACAGGCGUGAGCCACCAUGCCAGGCCCUCUCCUACCCUUUCUUAUGACCAAACAAUAGUCAUUUUUAUGGCUUCUAACUGGGAUGUAUGUGACUAUAGCCAAUGAAUAGAGAAAAGCUAACUGAAAUGAUACUGCCUUAUGGUAUAACAAGAAAACAAAUAAAUUUUAUUGACUUCCAUAUACCACUAGAUUAAGCAGACAAUCCAUUCAAAAUUUUCACUCUAAUUUUUUUUGCUAGUAUCUAUGGUAAUUUACAAUAAUAUUGAAUGAAUUUAAUUAUUGUAUUUUGAAGUUAUUAGAAAACUUCUCAAAUUAAAAGCUUUGAGUAUGCUAUUUAAUUUUAGAAUAUUCAGAUUGGUUUCAAUUAUUAAAAGUAAUGUCAUAUCAAUAUAUCAUCAUAGAUAGCAAGGUUUAGUGAUAUUAGUAUCUUAAAAUUUCUUGUUUUUUUUCUAAUCAAACAAGUCAAACAAUUUUGUAAUUUGUUUAUCUAAUUAAUUUUUUGUUUUCAUCUUCUUAUGUUAGUUUAUAUUAAAAUUUUUAAAAAGCUUCAUCAAAAAAUUAUAUCUUUCUGCUCCUUCUGAGCAAGUGCCUUCUAAGCUGAUGUUGCAUAGAAAACAGUUACAAGAGCAGAGGCCUGCAGGUAGUAGGAAAUAAAAACAAUAUUUUAUGGGUUUUCCCGUAAAAUAUUCCCAUAAAAUUUUAUCAGUGUUUUCCAAAAACUAAGUCUGUCAUACUGCCUAUUUAAGGUCAAAAUAAUUAAUGAUAGAUAAUUAACUCAGGGCCUUUAAAUCUGUGAAACCAUUUUAAUAAAGAGUAAAUGUUCCAUUGACGAAAGUUAGCAUCAUGUGAAGAGCUAUUCCCUACCGAAUAAGCCUGUGUUGUUAUCCACUUGCCUUAAGGAAUGCCAUUGUUUAUGAUGCCAGAUGAUCCAAAAACUAUGCAAAGCUUCAUUCAUCCUUCACAAAAGCCAAACAACCAGAAUAAUGACUGGCAAGAAGCAUGGUUUUAAUAAUCCAGGUAUGUCAAAUUUACUGCUUAGCUACAGAAUCAUCUCUCAUAACAUUAAUAUCUGAAUUUAUAACAAGUAAGACAAAGUUAGACGAUCUUUUAUUAACUACAAAAAUGCAAGUUUAUUCAUUUGUGAUAGGUUUUUCACCUUUGUCACUCUUACAUUUACAUAUCUGAUUUGGAAACACUUCAAAAAUGUGUGAGCUUCAAAUAAUGGCAUUGUCAAACGCAUCUAUUAAUAUUGUGAGCCUUCAAGUCAAAAUGAAACUCUUCCUGCUAUGCAAUACACUUUCCUAAUGAUGUUAUGAAAUGAUGCUUAGCCAGUAGUACAUUUGUCAAGAUUGUUCCUAGGCAUAGUCUUAACAGCAAUUUUUGAAAGUAAAUAUUUGGUUACUCAAUAUUUAAAUAUAUUUAAUACCUAAGAUGUAGUUCUAGGCAUGAAAAUCACUUAGAAUCAAUGAAGAGUAGACUCCUGGGUCAUUAAUAUAUAUGAAAAUUUAAAAAUAGUAUUUUAUUUAAUUUUAGUUUUUGUGAUGGGCUCUUACUGUCACCCAGGCUGGAAUGCAGUGCACUGUCACCACUCACUGCACCCUUGACCUCCCAGGCUCUGGUGAUCCUCCCACCUCAGCUUCCCAAGUAGCUGGGAUUAUAGGUGCACCCCACCACACCCAGCUAAUUUUUGUGUAUUUUGUAGAAAUAGGAUUUCGAUAUGUUGCCCAGGCUGGUCUCAAACUCCUGGCCUCAAGUACUGGGAUUAUAGGUGUGAGCCACUGCACCUGGCCUGAAAAUAGUAUUUUAAAUCAUUGUGAUAUCUUAAUACAUUUUCUAUUCUGUGUCCUUGACUAUUGAUAGUAGUAUUUUAGGUAACGAUGAGUAAAUCUUAAGAUUAUAUGGAAUAUUUUUAUUGUCUAAGUUUCUGACAUAUAUGAAGACUAAACAUAAUUAAAUAAUUAGAGUCCUUUCAAUUCUCUUGGAUAAACCCUGUCAUAACUUUUAGGAGAAAAUCUGAUUAAGUAGAUCACAUGAUUCCCUUCCUUGAAGCCAAACAGUUCUGGCUUCAGAGUCUUAGAAGAAUAUUGCAAGACAAGAAGAAUCUGCUGCCCCAUGGUGUUUGGUUUUCCCCCCAAGAGAUCAUUAGUAACCCAGUUUGUUCUCAGCUGCCCUAAAGAUAUAAUUUUAAUUGGUUUAUAUUAGCACUAGGUAUAUGUUUAAGGCUCAAUAAAUGUUAAAUGAACUAUUAGUAUUUCAUUGGAUAUAAACCAUAAGAUGGAAAUGAAAGAUUUUCACCAUUUCUGGUCAUUAUUCACCCAGGUUUACCUUUUCUUUCUCUGUAACUCAGCAACCUUCCCAUUAUCCAGGCACCUGGCAGAGCUACUGUUGUUAAAUUUCUGACAGCUUUUUCAUUACAGGCCCUGUUUUUCAAGAGGCAGGUUAACUAAGCGAUUUUGAUUUGUGCCAAGCUGAGAUGUGGAAUAGACACUUGAAGUCCAUUCUCCUGUUUUCCUAAGAUUUUAUUUGAAGUUAUUUGUCCUACUUUGAUCUAAAAAAUACUAAGAAAAAACUAAAAUUCACCUAUUAUUUUCAUUCAUGAUUUUUAUAACUGAGCAAAAGGAUGAUAAAUUCUGCUGUAGCUCUGCUUUUUAUUUUUUUUAUAAACCCAAGGCUUUUAAAAAAUUAACACAAGACAUUUCAUACUUCAGAGUUAUUAUUUGAUUCAGAAACAUAUUAACAGCCAAUUGUUUUACUUACAUGAGAUAGGGUAAGACCUUUUUAUUUUGUAAAACAUGAACCAAAUGCUAUAAUUUGUAUUUAUGUUAAACGUGUGACAUAUUCAUGUCAAAACAAUAUUUUUUGUCUCAUAACCAAGGACUCAUCUUUACUGUAGAAAACAUGAAAAAUGCAGAUAAGAGAAAAAAAAUUUAAAAUCAACCAACCCAGUAAGAUCAUAUUGGAUUUCAUUCUCUUUUUAUGUCCACUCAUUCUUCCCUGAAGUUUUAGAAACUUCUGGAAAGCAUUCCUGACUACCUCUCUGCCCCUUCCACAUACAGUUACCACAUUCUAAUCAGUUUUACCUGGUAUUUCCAUAUUCUUUCCACCUACUUCACACACGAUUCCAUGUGGUUUAGCAUCCACCCAGUUUACUAUACUAAAAUGUUUCUCUCAAAAUUUCCAGUAAGCUUCCUUAUCAUUGUCCAAGUACCAUUAUCUCCAUCUCUUUCUUGUCCACUGCAAUUUGUUUUAUGUUUGAAAAUCUCCUCACCUGGGUUCCACGAUGCUACCUAAUGUUUUUGUUCUCUUCUUACCUUUGCAACUAUUCACUGUCUCUUGCCUUUAAAUUUUCUUAUUAUUCAUUGAGUUUGGUGUAUAGGUUAAGUUGCUUUUACUUGUAAACAGUAGAAUAACCAACUAACAAUGGUGUAAACAACAGGAUAUUUAUUGAUUAUUUAACAAGAAGUCCAGAAGUUGGAAGUCCUAAGGCUGGUUUGGUGACUCAAAUAGGAACUCAAGGUUCUUUGCAUCCCUCCAUUGUCAUUGUCUGUCUUCUAGCAAUGUCUUGUCUCUUACGCAAAAGAUGGCUGUGUAGCUCUAAGAAGGCAGGAGGCUGAGGCAAAAUGGCCCUUCUGCUCCUUUAAUCAGGGAAAACACUUUUUUUUUUUUUUUUUUUUUCAGAAAUCUCCAUAAAUCACAUUGGCUAGAAAUGGGUCUUACACCCACCCCUACACCAGGGAAAAGUGCUAAUUGUGAUUCAUCCCUUGGUGGUGAGCACAAUGCCCCCUGACAUAAUCAGUCUUAGAGAAGCAAAAAAGAAAGGGCGAUGGCUGUGGGAUAUGUGACUGACAGGGGCUGCACGACUCGUCUGUCACCUAUGGCUGCUCUUCAAGACUGUGUCUAUUUUUCUCUACAACUGAAAGUCUCUGAGGUUCCAUUCAUGUGAUGCCCAAAACGGGUUGUUGUGAAAACCAGCUGGGAUGUGAAAGUACUGUAUAAACAGGAGUUGUAUUGUCUUUUAUUAAACGUACCAUAUUUUCCUAAUGAGAUGCAAUCUUUUUUUUGUCUUGUUUUUGUUGUUGUUUGUUUUGUUUUUUUUGAGACAGAGUCUCACUCUUUCUCCCAGGCUGGAGUGCAGUGGCGUGAUCUCUGCUCACUGUUACCUCCACCUCCAGAGUUCAAAGGAUUCUCCUGCUUUAGCCUCCCAAGUAGCUGGGACUGCAGGCACAUACCAUCACACCAGCGAAUUUUUUGUAUUUUUAGUAGAGAAGGGGUUUCGCCAUGUUGGCUAGCCUGGUCUCUAACUCCGAAGCUCAGGCAAGCCACUCUCCUUAGCGUCCCAAAGUGGUAGGAUUACAGGCGUGAGCCACCACACCCAGCAGAGACACAAUCUUAAAAUAAAUAUUUAGUAAUUCUUCUUGUGUAUUGAACCAAGCACCAACUCCUGCCAAUCCUUUCCUCAGAAUCUAUCUACAUCUUUCCAUUUUCCAUCGUCCUAUUCUAGGUAUCCGUUUACCUCAUGCUAUUUGUUUGCUUUUUUUUUUUUUUUUUUUUUGAGACGGAGUCUCCCUCUGUCACCCAGGCUGGGGUGCAGUGGCGGGAUCUCGGCUCACUGCAAGCUCCGCCUCCCGGGUUCUCGCCAUUCUCCUGCCUCAGCCUCCUGAGUAGCUGGGACUGCAGUGCCGGCCACCACACCCGUCUAAUUUUUUGUAUUUUUAGUAGAGACGGGGUUUCACCGUGUUAGCCAGGAUAGUCUCGAUCUCCUGACCUCGUGAUCUGCCCGCCUCGGCCUCCCAAAGUGCUGGGAUUACAGGCGUGAGCCACCGCGCCCGGCCUUUUUUUUUUUUUUGAGACGGAGUUUCUUUCUUGUUGCCCAGUCUGGAGUGCAAUGGCACGAUCUCGCCUCACCGCAACCUCUGCCUCCCAGGUUCAAGUGAUUCUCCUGCCUCAACCUCCCGAGGAGCUGAGAUUACAGGCACGUGCCAGCACGCCCAGCUAAUUUUGUAUCUUCAGUAGAGACGGGGUUUCUCCAUGUUGGUCAAGCUCGUCUCAAACUCCCGACCUCAGGUGAUCUGCCUGCCUCGGCCUUCCAAAGUGCUGGGAUUAUAGGCAUGAGCCACCGUGCCUGGCCUCGUUUGCUUCCUCUUGUAUGGCAUUUAUCCAUAUUCUUUUUUCCUACUACACACAAGAUGAAUACUACAGCUAGGAUUCCAGCCAUUAGCUGACCUUUUUGUCUAAACCAGAUGCCUGCUCCUCCAUAUGACCUCUCUCCUGUCUGGUCAGGCCUCUUCCAGGAACUUCCAUAACAUUCCAUUCUCAUUCCAAUCCCUUGUCUAGGCUCCUGCUGUGGCUCUCAGUGUUAACUGGAAUGUUUGACUUUGUCUCUUACACCACUGCAAACAGUGUGACAUUACUCAACAAAUGGACCAGGCAGGGUUAAGGUCACCAGUAAAGCAAGUUAUCUAAUUCUUUGGUCUGACUUGAGUUCACAAACCUACCCUAAACUAUUUGACUCUCCUGAUGGAAUUAAACUAAUCUAUUUAGUCAUUCGUCUCAUGUAAUAUCUUUGCCACAAAUCCUAAGAUCAUUUUAUAAGUAUAGGGACGGUGUGCAAUAGUCUAGUGCUAUAAAGUUGUAUUGAGUGCUCAUUCAAUACUUAACAAUUAGCUGAUCUUCAAAUAAUUUAAAACCACAUAUACUAUGCUUUUACCCAUUCUUCCUUUACCUCCAUUUAAAAUAAUGAAUUAUCUGCUAUACUGAGUCAGGGUAAAUUACAAUGAGUCCCAGGAUAAGGUGGUAGGACAGGAAGUGUGUGUUUUUACCCUCUUCCUCUGGAGUGCAUAAUGCUUUACUAUGAUACAAAGAGAAGUUUGAAGGAAGUCACGUUGUCAAAUAUGACAGAAGUAAUAACUUGACUGCAAUUCCUGAGCCUAUCAACCUCACCGUUUGUCCACAAACAUAACCAGAAUAUAUUUUAUCUUGAUUUCCGACUUGAGGGAAAAUAAGUUCAGUGAUUUAAGAUCUGCCAGUUAGCAUAAAUAUUGUGAAAGCAAAAAACUGUGCUAAAAUUUUAAGAGAAAAAAAGUUAAGUGUGUUGCGUUUUCAGAAAGAUUUAGCUAUGGAGUUUUUUUUUUUGUUUUGUUUUGUUUUUUUUUUUUUUGGUUUUGUUUUGUCUUGACCUAUGAGUUUGAAGAAGACAAAGUGGCUCUGUAAAUAAGUCGACUUCAUUUUUAAAGCGUUUGGAAAGGUUAAAUGAGGUUGAAUCUUGAGAGUCUUUUUGGUGGUUAGGAGAGGGGGAAUUUAUUAAAGAGAGGAAGACAAUGUACCUAAUAUGUUGUGAUGAUAAUGACAAACUCAAAGAUUUAAACUUCAUGAGUCAUUCUGGUCAUUCAUAUCAUCAUCAGGAAAACAUCUUCAUGUGUAGCUUCAUAGGUGAGCUCCACAAAACUGUGCAUUACCUUGUAGUAGUUUGUGAAUAAUGUGCUGACCUAUGACACAUAGCCACGUAAGUGAAUAAACACUAUUAUUAUUAUUAUUUUGUCUUGGUUUUCAUUAAACUAUCUUAGUAGUUUCAGGAGCUCUGGGUUUCAACACACACUUCUGCCAGCUGACUUUAGUGCGUCCAUUAGCAUAACAAAGUCAAUUAGGCAAACCUGAAUUUUCACUUUUAUCCCGUUCACAGAACAUCAGUGUAAAUGGAGACAGGAAGAAGAAAUUGGAUUGAUUCUCCACUUGAGAAUUAUGUUAACUUGGAAGAAAAUGUUAAGUCUACUAUGUGAGGGCAUCUAGUGAGAGGGAAGGAAUCACCUCCCUUCCCCCAUUAUGUCCCUUUAUGCACCUCUGACCCUUGUGCUCUCCUUUUCUUGUUGCUUCUGUGGUCUGGUUGUUAGCUUUCCCGAUCCUCCACACAUUAGAAACCUAAGCAUAAUGAUUUCUGAUCGAAGGCUAUGAGAUAUUUGAAAUAAAAAAAGGGGAAAUUGUUGAGUCUAGAACCAAACCUUUAAAAAUUAAGAACUACCAGUCUGUAAUGUGUGCCUUUAGAAAAAAACAAAGUCAAACAGAAAUUAGGCAACUAGUUAGAGCCGUGAUUGUGCUCUGCCACCCAUGAACUCCCGUCUAUGACUAUUUCCACUCUGGCUUUGUGUUUCAGUAGGUCAGGGACACAUAUUAAGAGCAACAAUUGGAACUGCGUUAUCCUUUACCUCCAUAAAAAUACAGCUUAAUAACAUGUUAAUGACUUAAAAUUACCUUGUCUUUCUAGAUUGUUUAUUGAUGUCAUUUCAGAUCGGUAUAAAGGAUGUGAAGUGAAUAAGAAAAUAGGGGAACACUUAAGAAUCUGUCCUCAGGAAUAUACAUGCUGCACCACAGAAAUGGAAGACAAGUUAAGCCAACAAAGCAAACUCGAAUUUGAAAACCUUGUGGAAGAGACAAGCCAUUUUGUGCGCACCACUUUUGUGUCCAGGCAUAAGAAAUUUGACGAAUUUUUCCGAGAGCUCCUGGAGAAUGCAGAAAAGUCACUAAAUGAUAUGUUUGUACGGACCUAUGGCAUGCUGUACAUGCAGAAUUCAGAAGUCUUCCAGGACCUCUUCACAGAGCUGAAAAGGUACUACACUGGGGGUAAUGUGAAUCUGGAGGAAAUGCUCAAUGACUUUUGGGCUCGGCUCCUGGAACGGAUGUUUCAGCUGAUAAACCCUCAGUAUCACUUCAGUGAAGACUACCUGGAAUGUGUGAGCAAAUACACUGACCAGCUCAAGCCAUUUGGAGACGUGCCCCGGAAACUGAAGAUUCAGGUUACCCGCGCCUUCAUUGCUGCCAGGACCUUUGUCCAGGGGCUGACUGUGGGCAGAGAAGUUGCAAACCGAGUUUCCAAGGUCAGCCCAACCCCAGGGUGUAUCCGUGCCCUCAUGAAGAUGCUGUACUGCCCAUACUGUCGGGGGCUUCCCACUGUGAGGCCCUGCAACAACUACUGUCUCAACGUCAUGAAGGGCUGCUUGGCAAAUCAGGCUGACCUCGACACAGAGUGGAAUCUGUUUAUAGAUGCAAUGCUCUUGGUGGCAGAGCGACUGGAGGGGCCAUUCAACAUUGAGUCGGUCAUGGACCCGAUAGAUGUCAAGAUUUCUGAAGCCAUUAUGAACAUGCAAGAAAACAGCAUGCAGGUGUCUGCAAAGGUCUUUCAGGGAUGUGGUCAGCCCAAACCUGCUCCAGCCCUCAGAUCUGCCCGCUCAGCUCCUGAAAAUUUUAAUACACGUUUCAGGCCCUACAAUCCUGAGGAAAGACCAACAACUGCUGCAGGCACAAGCUUGGACCGGCUGGUCACAGACAUAAAAGAGAAAUUGAAGCUCUCUAAAAAGGUCUGGUCAGCAUUACCCUACACUAUCUGCAAGGACGAGAGCGUGACAGCGGGCACGUCCAACGAGGAGGAAUGCUGGAACGGGCACAGCAAAGCCAGAUACUUGCCUGAGAUCAUGAAUGAUGGGCUCACCAACCAGAUCAACAAUCCCGAGGUGGAUGUGGACAUCACUCGGCCUGACACUUUCAUCAGACAGCAGAUUAUGGCUCUCCGUGUGAUGACCAACAAACUAAAAAACGCCUACAAUGGCAAUGAUGUCAAUUUCCAGGACACAAGUGAUGAAUCCAGUGGCUCAGGGAGUGGCAGUGGGUGCAUGGAUGACGUGUGUCCCACGGAGUUUGAGUUUGUCACCACAGAGGCCCCCGCAGUGGAUCCCGACCGGAGAGAGGUGGACUCUUCUGCAGCCCAGCGUGGCCACUCCCUGCUCUCCUGGUCUCUCACCUGCAUUGUCCUGGCACUGCAGAGACUGUGCAGAUAAUCUUGGGUUUUUGGUCAGAUGAAACUGCAUUUUAGCUAUCUGAAUGGCCAACUCACUUCUUUUCUUACACUCUUGGACAAUGGACCAUGCCACAAAAACUUACCGUUUUCUAUGAGAAGAGAGCAGUAAUGCAAUCUGCCUCCCUUUUUGUUUUCCCAAAGAGUACCGGGUGCCAGACUGAACUGCUUCCUCUUUCCUUCAGCUAUCUGUGGGGACCUUGUUUAUUCUAGAGAGAAUUCUUACUCAAAUUUUUCGUACCAGGAGAUUUUCUUACCUUCAUUUGCUUUUAUGCUGCAGAAGUAAAGGAAUCUCACGUUGUGAGGGUUUUUUUUUUCUCAUUUAAAAUAAAAAAGGAAGAAAGAAAAUAAUUUUCCUUGUAAAAUCGGGCCAAACCCCAAGACAGCUACAUUUUCAACAAAAAAGCAAACAGAGAAAAAUAAAUGAACUUUAACACUGUAAGUUCAGCAUUGACAGCCAACUUCCAGUGUAAGCUUUUUUGUGACAAAUCCGGGUUUAAAAAUGCUUAUGGGGAGAAAGCUUAAAGUUUGUUCUAAAUGUAGUGAAAAUGCACUGUUGUCUUGGAGGUAUCAUCUUGCACUCUAACCAAACAACACCAAAUUAAUCUGGAGGUACUGAUACUAAAUUUGGAAUCCCGUCUUUAAUAUGAGAACACAAAUUACUACAACUCAGUACCUCUGUCUUACUCUGCCCAAUUUCAAUUUAGUAAUGGCACCAUUAUUCUUAAUUCCCUUAAUGUCUGUCCGCUGUAUCCAAUUGGCACAGAUUUUCCCCUUCAUCUUCAAUUACUAGUAGCUACCCCCAUCAAUUCACCUUCCUCAAGAGUCUCAAUUGAAAAUAAUCUUUGAUGAUACAAUCUCUGCUUUUGCCACAGGUUUGACAUUAACUAGACGUUUCUGCCCCUGUGCUCAUUACCCUCCCAAAACAAUAGUUUUUUUAAUGAAUUGAAACACAAUUAGAUCCAUUCCUGAGUUUUCAUUUUUAACUAUUUACUUUGUGUCAGUUGGUUUCUGCAUCACAAGGGCAUUCUCUUACAAAACAACUCACAACAGAAAAAAAAAGUCAAGACAAAAAAUAUAUAUAUAUAGUAUUGACAUGGAGAUUUCUUUCACUUUUUUAGUCUUAGUAUGAUCAUCUAUUUUUAUAUCUAUGUAUAUAUAAAUCACAGAUUUUAACUUCUUAAUUCCAAGCUCAGGGUUGACACACCUUUGUAAGAAAAUGUUUUGUCAACCAGCUCUUCUUGUUUUGUGCUGCUCAAAGAAGGGAUUCCUCAGUGAUCGGUGAGCACCAAGAAUCAAGAAAGAGAACUUUUUAUGUAUCUAACUGUCCAUUUAUUAAAAAUUUGCCAGGGCACACCCUUCUGCAUGAGUGUGCUUCAGCCUGGGUGCUCCAGACUACACCAAACUCAUGGGAUGAGCCAUUGGUGUGCAGGGCUUUACCGGUGAUGGAAACUGUAUGUGUAAAGAAUGUUAUUCAUGAAAAACCAUUGCUUUCAUGUAAAACACCUUCGGCCUAGGAUUCCUGCCUGGCACUUGGAUACAUUACCUAACUCAAUAGGCCAGUUUAGAGCCACAGCCUAACCUGUUCACCAAGUAGGCCAAAGCCAGGCCUUUCGCUCCCCCUGACAGAGAGAAGCAAAAUAAACCCAACUGGGGGCUUUAUGAAUACAGUUGGCUAUCCAUAUGUUUCUUAGUUUUUAUGAUGCAUCUGGAGUAGGGAAAAGUAAUGUUUCAAGACACCAUAGUAGGCCAGUUACAUUUUAAUUAACUCAUCGACAGUAUUGACACGUAAAUGGUAUUUUUCAAUCUGUUCUCAUCAAAAUUAAAAUUAGUUAUUGAUUUAGUCAUCACAUUUAAGUAGAACACAUGUGGCACAAUAGUAUUAAGUAUAUUUGAGCACUUUUGCAAGACAGAAAGUAUUUACAAGCAUCUAUUGCUACUUUAUGCCUAAUGAAAUAUAAAAUGUAGGAUGAUGAGAGACUUUGUGGCAUUCUUUCAUUUAAACCUUUAUGAAAUUAACCAUCUAGUUCAUCAUUACAUACUCCUAGAAAACCAUCCAUUUCACUGCCCACAUUUUGGCUUCCUACCACAAAUUCCACAUAAGACUUCUCUAUGAAGGACCAGUCAUUUACAUUGCUCAUUUCAUUCUGUGUUCAGAAGUCAGUAUUGUCUUUCUCCAAUAAUUAAGGUGCAAUACAAAUUAAAUCAACCUUGAUUUUCCAGACUAUUUGAAUAAUAACUUGCUUUUAUGGCUUUAAACUCCAGGUCUUUCCUUUUUAAAAUAUUUCUGCAUUCUCUUUUAUGAACUAGAUCAGGAUGCCUUGUUUUUCCUGUGCUUUCACCCCCAAAAGGUUUUGUGCAUGUGUAUGAAUACACAUAAUAUUAGUGAAUGUGAACCCAUGUUCUAUACGCACUAAACACACAGUUAAUAUAUAAACGCCUGCUUCAUUUGUUUCAACACCUUCAUUAUCAAUAUGAUUCAUAUUGAUGAGAUAUAGUGAUGCAUAAUGAGCCAGGCAGAGAGCUGAAAUGAUAUCAGUUAAUGAUGUCACAGUGUUAGCACCCUGCAUGGAUGUGGUCAAAAUAUCAUUCAAGUUGUACUUCCUAGUUUUUAUCAUCAUACUACUAUGUCAUAUGAUUUUCAGACUAAUUUAACAUGAGAAAUGUUUUGGCCCUAAAGGAUUUCACUUAACCUAGUUACCCUAUUUCAGUAAGUAUUUUGGAAUUCAACCCUCGAAUUAUUUUUUCUCAUUUCAGCAUAGUGAUAGGGGAUGCAAUGAGGCUUCAUUAUUUUUUAUGACCUGCCCCUCAUUUGCUCUGAUGUUCCCUAAAUUCUGUAAUCAUAUCAUAACUUUUGUUAUGAAUAGAGAGGAAUGGGCUCACUGAAACCUGACACUAGAAAUUGGUGGGUGAUGCUCAUAACUGCAAACACUUAGCUUAUUGAAGUGCCUCUAUUUACAUGUUCUUUAGUUAUAAUAUGUAUUUUUCUAACAGAAAUACACGUCUGUAAUUGGUAUAUAUUAUACUUUGUAUGUGUCACAACAAAAGCUAAACAGAGGCUAAAGUCUUUAGCAGAGAAGAAUGAAUUACAAAUUUACCAAUAAGAGCUCUGUUUAUGGUUCUGUAUUGAAGGACAACCAUGACAACCUUCUGUCAUUUUCACGAAGGCCAAGUUGGUACUUUGAUUAUAGCCAUCGUAGAACAUUAGCACUAGAAAUCUGUCUCCCUUACAAUGACUUACCUAGCUAGCAUCAAGUAACUUGUAUCACCUGCUUUAAAUGUAAGGGAUAGAAAAUACUAUUUUGUCUACACUGAAAAACAUUAUUAUUCAUUGAUAAGUAGUAAUAAUUAUAAAAGUAACAUUCUUUAAAGCAAACACAUUGAAAAUAUUAUUACAGGCAGAACCCUGAUUUUUAAUUUAUAUUCCCUGCUGCAGACAUUAGCCUUCUUUAAUUCUUUUGCCAUUACAUACAUGUUUCGGCUACAGACUGAACACGAACUAAAGUCCCUAAGGAGGAAAAAACCUUAACAUAUUCCUGAGAUGUGAUUCUUUUAUUACUUCUUUUUGCAAAGCUAAUUAUCAAAUGAUUUGAUUAAACCUAGACGCAUUAGGAAAUGCAAGUUUUACCUAAAACUUGCAGAAAUUUAAACACAUUUCCAUUUACUUACUAACGAACAGACCUGAUUUUUAUUUAAAAACACAAUUUAGCUUUGCCAACAGAAGAGUAAAGGAAACCAUAACUUAUAAAUUUGUAAUGUGUUCCUCCUUGUUGGAGACAUUAGCCAGUGUUUAGUUUUAGACCAACUUAUACAAAGAGAGUAUUGAUUUGUACACAUUCUGGAGACUUGCUAUAUCAUGGUUUGCUAUGGCACAGACUCAGCUUAGCAUGGGGACAUUUUGAACUUCAUUCAAAGUUGAGUAGUUACUGGAACCUUUGACAUUGCCUUGUAAUGAGGUACUUCCAAAAAAAGACCCCUAACAAUGGCAUAAUAGUGAGGUCUCUCUGUGCAUAUACAUAAUAUAUAUGCAGGAUAAAUGUGUGCACCAAUCAAAUCUAAAAUUUUAUGUGACUGUCAAAUGAAUAUUAUUUGGGUUAAGAUUUUUCAUUUCUGAUUUGGAUAGAAAAUUGCUAUUAAUCUUGUAUUAAAAUAGUUUUUAAAAAUCUACCAGUGCCCUUUCUGCAUUUUCUUAAUUAUUGUCAUAGUCUAAAUUUCAGAGCCAUGGAAUUUUUUGUGUUUGAGACAUUUUUAGAAGCUUCAAUAUUAAAAAACAACAACAAACCUCGUAUAUUAAAACAGUGCCACUCUCCUAAGUACACUCAGCAUCUGAAAUCAGGAACUAUUUGAACUUUAGAACAUUUAGAGCUUCCCAAAUGUGUAUGGAAAAUACUGUAGCGCUGUUCUUUUGUACUGAUUUCUUCUCAGAGGAUAAAUUUAGUGACUUGAAAACUGAUGUCAAUACUUUAUAAAUGAGGUCAGAAAAUAAGAUCAAAUGUGAAAAGACUAAUAAUUUCCCAAUUUAGCCAAUUGCAUUGAUUUUUAUACUUCUGAAAUGUUUCCAUCCUCUCAGGCAUGCUAAAUAUUGUAUAACCUGCUAAAGAUUUAUUUCACAAAUGCUUAUUGAACUCUUAUUCUCUAUAAACCCUGCUCUAGGGGAUUUAUCACUGGCUGUGAAAAACCACCAGUUGAAAAUUAUUCAUUCCUUAAUGCAGCUAAUCAUAAUUAUUACAGAUAAAUAAUGUAUUUCAAGAAUGAUCUUAUAAAUAAAGGAACCCAUACAAACAAA